UUUCACUGUUGAGAGGAUUAUAGCUGUUAGGAGGUGAAUGUGCUAUUCUGAUUUUCGGAAUGCAAUCUCAUUUUCACAGGGCCUCCGGGAUUUGGCUCUGCCUUCAACUGGGGUGAGAGGGCUUAAAUCCUCCUUCACCCAAAGUCCUGGAGGAGGCCUCCACACUCUCUGGCUCUCCCACACUCUCUGGCUCUCUGGUGUGUCUUUGAUCAGCACACCCCAGGGCUCUGACCUGUUUCUGACCACCUGCUAUGUGGAUGAAGAUACAUCUGGGGCCAAGUGAGAAGACCCAGUAGCACCAGGUUUCGCCCCAAAGGAGAGAGGGAGACACGGAGGAUGGUGGAUUUUCCAGGCUACAAUCUGUCUGGUGCAGUCGCCUCCUUCCUAUUCAUCCUGCUGACAAUGAAGCAGUCAGAAGACUUUAGAGUCAUUGGCCCUGCUCAUCCUAUCCUGGCCGGGGUUGGGGAAGAUGCCCUGUUAACCUGCCAGCUACUCCCCAAGAGGACCACAAUGCACGUGGAGGUGAGGUGGUACCGCUCAGAGCCCAGCACACCUGUGUUUGUGCACAGGGAUGGAGUGGAGGUGACUGAGAUGCAGAUGGAGGAGUACAGAGGCUGGGUAGAGUGGAUAGAGAAUGGCAUUGCAAAGGGAAAUGUGGCACUGAAGAUACACAACAUCCAGCCCUCCGACAAUGGACAAUACUGGUGCCAUUUCCAGGAUGGGAACUACUGUGGAGAAACAAGCUUGCUGCUCAAAGUAGCAGGUCUGGGGUCUGCCCCUAGCAUCCACAUGGAGGGACCUGGGGAGAGUGGAGUCCAGCUUGUGUGCACUGCAAGGGGCUGGUUCCCAGAGCCCCAGGUGUAUUGGGAAGACAUCCGGGGAGAGAAGCUGCUGGCCGUGUCUGAGCAUCGCAUCCAAGAUAAAGAUGGCCUGUUCUAUGCGGAAGCCACCCUGGUGGUCAGGAACGCCUCUGCAGAGUCUGUGUCCUGCUUGGUCCACAACCCCGUCCUCACUGAGGAGAAGGGGUCGGUCAUCAGCCUCCCAGAGAAACUCCAGACUGAGCUGGCUUCUUUAAAAGUGAAUGGACCUUCCCAGCCCAUCCUCGUCAGAGUGGGAGAAGAUAUACAGCUAACCUGUUACCUGUCCCCCAAGGCGAAUGCACAGAGCAUGGAGGUGAGGUGGGACCGAUCCCACCGUUACCCUGCUGUGCAUGUGUAUAUGGAUGGGGACCAUGUGGCUGGAGAGCAGAUGGCAGAGUACAGAGGGAGGACUGUGCUGGUGAGUGACGCCAUUGACGAGGGCAGACUGACCCUGCAGAUACUCAGUGCCAGACCUUCGGACGACGGGCAGUACCGCUGCCUUUUUGAAAAAGAUGAUGUCUACCAGGAGGCCAGUUUGGAUCUGAAGGUGGUAGGUCUGGGUUCUUCCCCACUGAUCACUGUGGAGGGGCAAGAAGAUGGAGAAAUGCAGCUGAUAUGCUCUUCAGAUGGGUGGUUCCCACAGCCCCACGUGCAGUGGAGGGACAUGGAAGGAAAGACGAUACCAUCCUCUUCCCAGGCCCUGACUCAAGGCAGCCAUGGGCUGUUCCACGUGCAGACAUUGCUAAGGGUCACAAACAUCUCCGCUGUGGACGUCACUUGUUCCAUCAGCAUCCCCUUUUUGGGCGAGGAGAAAAUCGCAACUUUUUCUCUCUCAGAGUCCAGGAUGACGUUUUUGUGGAAGACACUGCUUGUUUGGGGAUUGCUUCUUGCUGUGGCUGUAGGCCUGCUCAGGAAGAGAAGGUGA